CAGGCGCGGUGGCUCACGCCUGUAAUCCCAGCGCUUUGGGAGGCCGAGGCGGGUGGAUCACCUGAGGUCAGGAGUUCGAGAGGAGCCUGCCCAACAUGGUGAAAUCCAGUCUCUACUAAAAAUACAAAAAAUUAGCCAGGUGUGGUGGUGCAUGCCUGUAAUUCCAGCUACCUGGGAGGCUGAGGCAGGAGAAUCGCUUGAACCCUGGAGGUGGAGGUUGCAGUGUGCCGAGAUCCUGCCAUUGCAUUCCGGCCUAGGCAACAAGAGCAAAACUCAAUCUCAAAAAAAGAAAAAAAAAAAAAGGGAAAGGUAGAGGUAGCCCGAAUAUAAUCUUAGAUAUGGCAUCAUAAGGUUGUGUUCAAGUUCCAGAUAUGUUAACUUGGGCUGGCCAUCCAAGACCUGGCAAGACCUCUUUGAGGCCAUUUCCUUACAAUAUUGUUAAAGGUUAAAUGAGAUACUGCUAAAUGAGAUAUUGCACGUGUAAAUUAUGAAGUACUUCUGAAACAAGAGAAGCUUGAAACUACUACCACAAGAAAUGUGAUACAGUAUGAACAAGAGAUGAAGUAAAGCACAGCCAAGCAGCAGGGAGGGUAAAGGUGAAGUUCAAAGCAAGAAUAUAUAGCAAACCCAAGUCCACACAGUUUUUGUGACUUCCUCCAGCCUACUGGAGAGGCGAAUGCCGAUUUUGAGAGUAGAUGCAAGAAGGACAAGAGGCUGAAAAAAAUCUAGGUAAGGACUAUUUAAAAAUCUUUGGAGAUAUGCUUAACAUUUGGAAAUUACUUGCACAUUUUAUAUAAAGGUGGCAUUUGACUCAUUGGCGUGUUAUAUUUUGGAAAUGGCCAAACAUUUCAUUUUUAUAUUUUAUAAUGGUUUUUUUUUUUUUUUUCAUAUUUUGGGGUUAACUUUUUUUCAGAUUCCAUACUUUUAAAAGCUUAGGCUCCAGACACUAUGCCUAUAGCAUGAAACAGAUAAUGAAGGAAUCAAGUGAAACAGUCGCCCACUGGGUACAAAUUAAGUAGGGAAGGUCAUGAACAAAGAAAGCAGUGAGGGCCCAGUAGACAAGCUGACGCAACUGGAGAUAACAACAGGUGGAGGGGAAAGGAGCAGCUGUUUCCAUUUUUGGAAUUUUGGAGAAUCAGGAGACGCCUGGUAAGGCCAGAGAAGGUGGCCGUGUAAUUAUAAAGUUAAAGGGGUCGGACGUGUUCAUCUUCCCAAUUAGUUUUAAGCCCACAAAGGGCUUGUCCCUCAUUGCCACCGUCCAUUGUCUCACUGUGACCAGGCAGGAGCCCUCCGUGAUUGACUGAUAAAAACAGCGGGUCCAACUCGCUCAGCUCGUUUCUGUUACACAGGACUGUGGAAUCCCGGGUGACAUUCAACUCCUUAGGUCAUCUGCACUCCCCCCGGACCGGAAAACAAAGCCUUCCCGAGCCCGACAAGGAGGGUGGCGCUCCCUGGCCCGGCCGAAGUAAGCCCUCCAUUCGACACCUCGGCUCCACGGUCUCCCGAACCGGUCCCCGUAACGCGAGCCUGAGAUGCCCUCACCCCCGAAAAAUACCCAAAGUCGGGGAGCCGCGGGAGUGCUUGUACCCAGCACGCUAGGCCUGAGGGACCUGUGAGCUACAGUAAGCGCCUGAGGACAGAGGGGAGCCUCGCAGCCUCAAACCCGCGUGGAGGAGAAACGUCUGGCGCCCCCGAGCGGCCGAGACCUCGGGAGCCCGAAAAACGUCUCCCACUCCCAGCGCAGAGCCAACUGACAGUGCCAUCCACCAAUGGGAGAACCCAGUCUGCGUUCGUGGGACGAGUCCGAGGGCAGAAAGAAGGCCGUCCCGGCGCCAAAUCAGCGUGGCUUUUUAAGAGGUCCUGAGGCCUCUCUGGUCACCACAGAGAGAGGGACAGUCCCUGUGAAACGGUGACGCUGACUACACUAUGCCGCUCGCUCCGAGCCUUGGCCUUUUCCUCCCGCCGCACUCUAAGCCCUUCGGCCGCCCCGCCCACGGCCUUGUCAGGUCCCGCCCCCCGCGUGGACCUGCCCAUGGGUGGAGUGAAGGCUUUAACCAUAGACCACCUGGCCGUGAAUGAUGUGAUGCUGGAGAGCCUACGUGGGGAAGGCCAGGGCCUGGUGUGUGACCUGUGCAACGACAGGGAAGUAGAGAAGAGGUGUCAGACCUGCAAAGCCAACCUCUGCCACUUCUGCUGCCAGGCUCAUAGGCGGCAGAAGAAAACGACUUACCACACCAUGGUGGACCUAAAAGACUUGAAAGGCUACAGCCGGAUUGGGAAGCCCAUCCUGUGUCCUGUUCACCCUGCAGAGGAACUGAGGCUGUUCUGUGAGUUCUGUGACCGGCCCGUGUGCCAGGAUUGUGUGGUGGGGGAGCAUCGGGAACACCCCUGUGACUUCACCAGCAAUGUCAUCCACAAGCAUGGGGACUCUGUGUGGGAGCUCCUCAAAGGUACUCAGCCCCACGUGGAGGCCCUGGAGGAAGCCCUGGCUCAGAUCCACAUAAUAAACAGUGCCCUCCAGAAGCGAGUGGAGGCAGUGGCAGCUGAUGUCCGGACAUUCUCGGAGGGCUACAUUAAGGCCAUUGAGGAGCAUCGGGACAAGCUGCUGAAGCAGCUGGAAGACAUACGGGCCCAGAAGGAAAAUUCCCUGCAGCUGCAGAAGGCCCAGCUGGAACAGUUACUGGCAGACAUGCGGACUGGAGUGGAGUUCACCGAGCACUUGCUGACCAGCGGCUCAGACUUGGAGAUCCUCAUCACCAAGAGGGUGGUGGUAGAACGGCUCAGGAAGCUGAACAAAGUUCAAUAUAGCACCCGUCCUGGAGUAAAUGAUAAGAUACGCUUCUGUCCUCAGGAGAAAGCAGGCCAGUGCCGUGGCUAUGAAAUUUAUGGUACGAUUAAUACCAAAGAGGUUGAUCCAGCCAAAUGUGUCCUACAAGGAGAAGACCUCCACAGAGCCCGGGAGAAACAGACGGCCUCUUUCACCCUGCUUUGUAAGGAUGCCGCAGGAGAAAUCAUGGGCAGGGGAGGAGACAACGUUCAAGUUGCCGUUGUCCCUAAAGAUAAGAAAGACAGCCCAGUCAGAACAAUGGUCCAGGAUAACAAGGAUGGGACAUACUACAUUUCCUACACCCCCAAGGAACCUGGCGUCUAUACUGUGUGGGUCUGCAUCAAAGAACAGCAUGUGCAGGGCUCGCCAUUCACUGUGAUGGUGAGGAGAAAGCACCGCCCACACUCAGGCGUGUUUCACUGCUGCACCUUCUGCUCCAGCGGGGGCCAGAAAACCGCUCGCUGCGCCUGUGGAGGCACCAUGCCAGGUGGGUACCUAGGCUGUGGCCAUGGACACAAAGGCCACCCAGGUCAUCCCCACUGGUCAUGCUGUGGAAAAUUUAAUGAGAAAUCUGAAUGCACAUGGACAGGUGGGCAGAGCGCACCGAGGAGUCUACUUAGGACUGUGGCUCUCUGAUGGGUUUGUGCUCAGCCUUUUAAAGCUGCAGGCAGCACCACUUGAGAUUUCCAGAGGACCCAGACCUUCGUUCAUUCUAAAGAGACUGAUAGAAUUAAAAACAAAGUGCCUUAUCUUGCACUGGAGUUCAAGUGCUCUUUUGUUAGUUAUUCACUGAUUGUACUUGUGGAUGGUUGAGCACAAAAAACCACCUCUACAUUUCUCUUAAAGGUAGGUUGGCAACGUUCUUUUUCUACCACAGGAUACUCCUUUUCAUUUUGUACAGUAUGGAGGUAUCUAUUCCAUUGGCACUGAAGGGUCUAGGUAGUUUAGUUCCUUUCUGAUAUAACCCUUUUUUUUUCUUUUUUUUUUUUUUUUAAAGACAGAGUCUCACUCUGUCACCCAGGCUGGAGUGCAGUGGCAUGAUCUCGGCUCACUGCAACCUCUGCCUCCCGGUUCAAAUGAUUCUCGUGCCUUGGUGUCCCGAGUAGCUGGGAUUACAGGUUCCCCCCCACCUUCCCCCACACCCAGCUAAUUUUUGUGUUUUUAGUAGAGACGGGGUUUCACCAUGUUGGCCAGGCUGGUCUCAAACUCCUGACCUCGUGAUCCACCUGCCUCGGCCUCCCAAAGUGCUGGGGUUACAAGCAUGAGCCACCACACCUGGCCUAUUAUGACCUUUUUCAUUUUUCUCUGAGCUACACAUUAUUUAGAUAUUUCCCCUAGAGAUUAGAAACCUCCUUUCAUCCUGUCCACUUUUUGUUAGCAUACUUUCAUUGGAUUUACUGGUACAUGUUUUGUGAUCAUGAUAAUGUGAUCUUGUUUUGGUGGUGUCCCCCUACUCCGUCUCUAUGCCAUGACAGCCUUCUGCCCCAAAGCCUGGAAGAUUACUCUUUGGUCAAGGGCAUACAAAUAGAAAGUUAAUAAAGGGGAAUGGUGUUGAAAUAGAACCUCAUACAUUUAUUACAGUUCUACUUAUACAGAAAAUCUAGACACCUUCAUCCUUCUCACAGCUCUGUUUUUUAGUAGAGUAGUCUUUAGAGUAGUCUUCACUGUUAUCUAUAUACCUAGAAAGUUAACUGGGAGCUUUGACUCUUACUGUGCCUUCACUCAUAGUGUGCCUUCUUAGCUGCUGGAGAAUUUGGGGAGAGGAUGUACACAGCACUGGUGCCUCAGCCCUGCCAAGGUCUUCACUGUAUAUAUUUUGUGUGUUCUUCUGAAACUCUUGAUUUCUUAUAUGGCAAUAAACUCAGCAUGUAUUAAAUAUAA